ACGCGCGCCGGCGACCAUGGCGUUCGCCGGGCUGGAGCGAGUACAUUAACCCCUGGAGGCGGCGGCGGCGGCGAGGGAGCGAGCCUCGAGCGGGCGGGCCCCAGCCUGAGGGAAGGGAGGAAGGGGCGGGGAGAGCGCCAGAGGGAGGCCGGUCGGCCGCGGGCGGGCGGGCAGCGCAGCGCCGAGCGGGGCCCGCGGGCCCAUGAGGAGGCCUGGGGACCAUGGGCUCCAGGAUCAAGCAGAAUCCAGAGACCACAUUUGAAGUAUAUGUUGAAGUGGCCUAUCCCAGGACAGGUGGCACUCUUUCAGAUCCUGAGGUGCAGAGGCAAUUCCCGGAGGACUACAGUGACCAGGAAGUUCUACAGACUUUGACCAAGUUUUGUUUCCCCUUCUAUGUGGACAGCCUCACAGUUAGCCAAGUUGGCCAGAACUUCACAUUCGUGCUCACUGACAUUGACAGCAAACAGAGAUUCGGGUUCUGCCGCUUAUCUUCAGGAGCGAAGAGCUGCUUCUGUAUCUUAAGCUAUCUCCCCUGGUUCGAGGUAUUUUAUAAGCUGCUUAACAUCCUGGCAGAUUACACGACAAAAAGACAGGAAAAUCAGUGGAAUGAGCUUCUUGAAACUCUGCACAAACUUCCCAUCCCUGACCCAGGAGUGUCUGUCCAUCUCAGCGUGCAUUCUUAUUUUACUGUGCCUGAUACCAGAGAACUUCCCAGCAUACCUGAGAAUAGAAAUCUGACAGAAUAUUUUGUGGCUGUGGAUGUUAACAACAUGUUGCAUCUGUACGCCAGUAUGCUGUACGAACGCCGGAUACUCAUCAUUUGCAGCAAACUCAGCACUCUGACUGCCUGCAUCCACGGGUCUGCGGCGAUGCUCUACCCCAUGUACUGGCAGCACGUGUACAUCCCCGUGCUGCCGCCGCAUCUGCUGGACUACUGCUGUGCUCCCAUGCCCUACCUCAUAGGAAUCCAUUUAAGUUUAAUGGAGAAAGUCAGAAACAUGGCCCUGGAUGAUGUCGUGAUCCUGAAUGUGGACACCAACACCCUGGAAACCCCCUUCGAUGACCUCCAGAGCCUCCCAAACGACGUGAUCUCUUCCCUGAAGAACAGGCUGAAAAAGGUCUCCACAACCACUGGGGAUGGUGUGGCCAGAGCGUUCCUCAAGGCCCAGGCUGCUUUCUUCGGUAGCUACCGAAACGCUCUGAAAAUCGAGCCGGAGGAGCCGAUCACUUUCUGUGAGGAAGCCUUCGUGUCCCACUACCGCUCCGGAGCCAUGAGGCAGUUCCUGCAGAACGCCACACAGCUGCAGCUCUUCAAGCAGUUUAUUGAUGGUCGAUUAGAUCUUCUCAAUUCCGGCGAAGGUUUCAGUGAUGUUUUUGAAGAGGAAAUCAACAUGGGCGAGUACGCUGGCAGUGACAAACUGUACCAUCAGUGGCUCUCCACUGUCCGGAAAGGAAGUGGAGCAAUUCUGAAUACUGUAAAGACCAAAGCAAAUCCGGCCAUGAAGACUGUCUACAAGUUCGCAAAAGAUCAUGCAAAAAUGGGAAUAAAAGAGGUGAAAAACCGCUUGAAGCAAAAGGACAUUGCCGAGAAUGGCUGCGCCCCCACCCCAGAAGAGCAGCUGCCAAAGACUGCACCGUCCCCACUGGUGGAGGCCAAGGACCCCAAGCUCCGAGAAGACCGGCGGCCAAUCACAGUCCACUUUGGACAGGCAAAUUUUCAAAAAUUUUGAGGAGACAGCACGGCUGAGGUCAUAAAUGAGCGGGACUGUUGAAUGAAGUCAUUAAAUGCACUGCUGCCUCCCGUACUCCAAGGCACUCUGCUUAAGGUGCCUCUGUUAGCUAAGCAUCUCAUUAGAACACUUUAGCAUCCCGGGCCCUUCUUUGCACCUUCAAAUAAAAGGCAACAAGCGAAGUCUUAAAAAAAAAAUCAAUUAGGAGUUCUUUAUUAAUGUACUUCCUGAAAAUCAAUAUCAGGAGUCGUGCUUCUGAGAGUAAACACCCGUGCUACAAUUCUAGAGAUUCAAUUUUUUAAGCAACUGUUUUCAACUACCUGAGCAUUAGAAAAAUUGUCUAUUUAAUUUUUUUUCCCUUAAGUAAAACAUUCCACUCUGUAUAGAAACUAAAAUUUUGUAUCCCCUUCCUACUUGUAAUUAUAUUUUUGGUUAAAAAAGAUUAUGUACCCUUUCCUACCUGUCCUGAAUUGACUUUUGGUUAGCGAAAGUCAUCAUUUGGAGAGAUUUAUGAGAAAUGGCUCUUUUAGCAAGAUAUGGCUGUAACAAGAAUUUGCAAGGUUAUUUAUUUUUAAAUCACCUGAUUCUGUAGCCAUUUAUUAGAUGAUGCAUGAUUAAGAGUCUUCAUGAUUUUUAUCUUAAAUGUGAUUGCUAUUUCACCACAUGUAAAGGACCUAGAAGCCUACAUUCCUGUUUUAAACAGACCUUUAUCAGGUGCCUACUAUGCACCAGGCAUUGAGCUAUUCAGAAAUGAACGAAACUCACAAAAUUCUUGCUCCAGGUUACUACUGUAAGGGGUGAGUUGGUUGGAACAUAAAAGUCACUCUUCUCUAAUCAAUAUUUUCAGAUAAUAUAUGUUUAUACAUCUUUAACUUGGGGAGGUUCAUCCCCUUUUCUGAUUUUAUACUUAAAAGGAUGUUAUAAAAAUUGAAACGCAAGAAAGAAGAAUCCACAGGGUGAUACUCAUUUAGUUAAUAAGUAUUUUCAAAUUGCACUGGUGUCUGCUCCCCUGAAGAGCUGCCUCCCCCCAGCUCCAGGCUCAGGCCCUGUUGGAGCAAUCUGCACCCCAGUUCCCUGGCUGUGUUUGCUGAAAGCACAGCCCCUGGUUGUCGCCAGCGUGGCAUUCCAGAGUCAGCUUCCUGCUUUCCUUUGUCCUCAUUCCUGCACACACUAACCUUCCCAUGAAAGGAGCCCCUCACUGGAGUUUGGAGCCCAUUACAGAGAAAGAGGGGGCGGGGGAGAGGGAUUUCAUGGUGUUAAACAUUCCAUUUUCGAAACACAAAAAAAGGAGGCCCUAUUUGAAAUGGAGAAAGACCUUCUUUCCAUUUCAGCCAGAAGUAGAGAUUCUUUAAUGUCAUUCCCAGCUAAAUGCAGAAUAAGAGUAUGUGUGUGUGCACGGGUGGGGGAUAAACAAUUAAAAAAGCCACCCCAAACUCUGUUGAAAUAAGAGCUGUCUGUGCCUUCACAGGUCUGCAAACUGGAGAGGAUGAAAGUGGCUUUUUUUCCCUGUUUGUCACUUCCCUCACGUGGCUGCCAGCAUUAUGCAAGUGUACAGGAAGGCAGGAUUUUUUUUUUUAAUGCAUGCAUGCGGAUUAAGGUCAAGCCCCUAGUAUCAGCCAUGCAGCGGGCUCUCCCUUCCAGCUGCAGCCGCAGAGCCUACCCACAGCCGCGAGAUGCCUUAAUUGAGACGUGCUGUCAAAGUGACAAACACAUUUGCAUACAGUCUACACUCUAUUUAUUUUCUCUGGAAAGGUCUACAGUCUGCUGUUGGUUGAACAUUCUUAAUCAGUUUGCUGUAAGUGAACUGCCAGCUAGCUCACUUAUGCCGGCCCCUUCUUCAUUAGGUGACAGAUUAGCUGCAGAGGGAGGGGGGCUUGAGCCAGGGAAACCACAGACCCCUUUCUUUUAACUCUUUCCAGCUUUGCCCUUAUGGUAGGUUGUCCUUGAGUCUUUUCCCGGGUCCCUGGUUUGAUGGGCUGUUGACCGUAAGAAGUACGGUUUCUAGAGCACCUACUACCGGCAGGCAUGAGUUUUAAGGACUUGAUAUUCUUCCCAAAGAACAGUCUCUUGAGUUUCAUUUCAGAAGUUUUUACCACACUCUCUUACCAUCUAUACUAUUUUCUUUACUUGAUAGUUUUCUUUAAAUAAGACUCAGACCUGACAUCUAUAGCAUCUUAGCCUCAUCUUCAGAGAUGCCAUUGGUAAAAUUAUAGGCUUGAUAUACUAGUCCCAGUUUUUUCUAACAUAUAAAACAAUUUUAAGUGUUCAUCUAUGAAUCACCUAAUGCACUCACGUAGCCCUAAUGGUAUAUAUUCUCUUUUUUUGGAAACCAACAGACUCCUUGGUAUCUUUUUUGUUGUCUCCACCACAUCCCUUUGAGGAAGGGACCAUUAGCCCCAUUUUAUUGACCCAGAGCUGGAGCUCAGAGACGUGAGAGAACCUGCCCAGGGCCACUUCACCAGCUUGGAAACCCAAGCCCAGACACCUCCUCUCGAGCCCACACCAGCUCUCAAAACAAGCAGGGACUGCAGCCAUGUGAUAUGUCUGUUAAAGCUACUGUACCCUGCCCUGGCAAAAUCAUCUUAACCAGCCAGAGAGAGCACCUAUUUUAACCUCAAAAAAAUCCUCGCCUUGGGUCUGUGUUUCUGUGGAUUUCGUUAUUUAAGAAGAUUUAGCUUGCCAGUGGGGAUGGAGACCGUUGAGACGGUUGCCUUCAUCUCACCACCUGGCAAAGCCGGUGCCUGUGCAGCUAGCCAGGGCAGCUCCAUGGAGACCUCUGACGGCAGCUCUGCAGCGGGGGCUGGCAAGAGGGGAGCUUAGUGUCGAGGCAAGAGCUGCUACUGCCAGGGGAGAGAAGGUGCUGCCUUGCCCUCUGCCUCAGUGGAGUUCCUCUUUCCAAGCUGUGAUCAUUCCUCCAUUUAAGUAUCAUCUAUUCAUCUGUCUGUUGAGACCUACCAUGUGUAAGAUAAAUAAGUUCUCAGUCCCUACCAUUGUGGGGCAUAAUGAUGAGACAGACCAGCAGAUGGACAGGCCCAAUCAGAGGGAUAAAGACAAUGAGGGAAGUAGGCUCCAAGCACUCCCAGGGCCCCCCAGAGGCUCCCUCUUCAUCUCCAGGCCCACUUCAUAGUCAUAGUCACUUCAUAGUCAGUCAUAGUCCACCUCAUAGUCCCAAGUUGGACACUUUAAUUAAAAGAUGCUUUUGUCAGUAGCCUGACCAACAUGGUGAAACCCUGUCUCUACUAAAAAUACAAAAAUUGGCCGGGUGUCAUGGCAGGCACCUGUAAUCCCAGCUGCUCGGAAGGGUGAGGCAUGAGAAUUGCUUGAACCCAGGAUGCAGAGGCUGCAGUGAGCUGAGAUCGCACCACUGCACUCCAGCCUGAGUGACAGAGCGAGACCCUGUCUCAAAAAAAAAAAAAAGAUAUUUUGUCAACAAACUGAACUCGCUAAUAAUUUGUUUUCUAAAGCAGACAUAUGUUAGGCCACUCAGCUUAUAAGAGCAAAGUAAAUAGGUUUCUAGUUAGCCUCUGCCUCCUGAUCACGUAGUUUCUUUAAGAAUUCAAAAGUGUCAACUUGAGAAUGCCUAUUCCUGCCUUGGAAGAUGUCGCAGUUUAGAGAGGCUUUAAAUUACUGUUUUCCCCUUCUCAAGUUUAGUAUCAUUUGGGAAACAAAGCCCAGGGGACAGUCAAAUGAGAUAAAAGUGCCAGCUGUGUUUAUUGAUAAGCCUGAAAGGAGAAUAUUGCAUUAGACCUGAAGGCAAAUGUUGCAAACACUUCACCUGAGAAUGUGAAGACCGCGUUUCUCCACUCGAGAUAAGUGGACAAUGGCAGGUCUCUCCAGGUUGGAGCUGCCCAUAGACUCCUAGCAAGGAGGAGCUGCGGGAGGGCGUUGCCCUGGCUGCUCCCCAGGAGGGAGCUGGAAGGGGUGAUGGAGCUCAGUUCCUUCUCCCAGACUCCCCGGGAAGGCAUUCUUCCUCUUCCUCUGGGAGGGGUUGAACAAGAGGGUGCCUGGCCAAGCCAAGGAUUCCCCCCUGGUUUUCUCUCCUAGGGUAGGAAAUGGAAGCUCCUCCUUCCCACAGCUAUAGAAGGAGUGAGUGAGUGGUGUCCUCCCCGGCAGCCCUGGGCACCCCUUGGUUAGAAUGGCUGGCCUUGACUGGCUUCCCUCCCGAGGACCCCUGUGGAAACUGCUCUGCUCCCUACAUUUAAUAAGAUGGGUGAGCCAUAGAUGCUUUCACAUCCGUGAGCACUGACUUGAGACUUUGCCAUCAGCGGGUGAGGAAGAAAUCAUUUUACCCAUCGUACACAUGAGGAGGCACACUGGAACGGCGUUGCUGGAAUGAGUAGCUAAUUCCUACUCCAAAUCCAGCAGCAGCAGCACCUCUGCUUCUCUUGGCUGUGUGCAGCUCUCCCUCCUUGCCAGGAGAAUGGCCUGAUUGUGUGAGUUCAGUGACACUGGACCCUAGUCCUAGGUGCAGAUAGCCAAGGCUAGAGACUGAGGCUUCCCUGAGAAUAUCACAGCAAACCCCUUCCAGGGCCCCCUUCUUUGUAUUUCCUCCAAAUGACUGAUCUGCAAACAAAGUAGUUGCCUGCCUUCCAAUCUGAUAGAUUGCAAAAAGCAUGUAUUGAAAGGUGCUGCCUCUGUUCUUCUCCCAUCUGAACAAAGGUUUCUAAACCUCUUUAAUGUAAAGUUUGAAAAGCUGGUUAAACCAAAACCAAAACCAAGCACCACCGUGGCUUCCAGAGAACUGUGGCAGGGAGGUCUGGAUAGCAGCCCCAGGAACAGCUCUUGGGAUGUGGUUGCCGGCUUGUCUCUGCGUAUGGAGAAUUCUGGCAUCAGGGUCAUCAGCCAGGUCAUUUAGUGCCAAUCCCAUGCUAGGCUGGAGAAGAUGCCGAGCUAGCAAAUGCCUUCUCAGCACCCUUGGCUCUGAGUGCCCUGAGAGAGUCCUCUUGCCCCACUGAGCUUGGAAGCCACAUGCAAUUCCCUUCACUUCAGCCAUUGCCUCCUCACCACCUCCAGCAGGUGCUCCCAUGUUCUCAGGAUACUGCACACCCCAGGCCUCUGGUCUGAACAUACACUCCCCACCAAACUCACUCCUCCAUCUUCCACCCCAGUGAAUGACACAGGCUGGCCAUCCAGAGCCAGGCUCCGCCCUCCUUCUCCCCAGAUCCUCUCCUUCCACCCCUGAACACUACUUCAUCCUCUCCUCUCCAUCACCUUUGCCACAGCUGUGGUGCAGGCAGCAUAAUCAUUCACCUGGACUGUUUCACAGGCUCCUAACUGGUACUCCCUGUAGUCCCCAUGUGGCCUUGCCGGGUCCACUGUAAGCCGGGUCCACUGUAAGCAUGCACUUACUGUAAGCAUGCACUAGUGGCCGCCUCACCCCCGCUCCCAGCCUCUCCUAAAGACUCCAUCUUCCUCCUUGGCCCCUUUGUGACCUGCCUGUCCAAUCCCAGAGCAGGCCUCCUGGUAAAUUCUCCCAACUCCCCUAGGAAGAGUGAGUUGCUUCUGUCCUCGUGCUACCCCAGGACUAUGCACACGCCGCUUGUCACGCAGCCCUGCAAUUUUUCUUUAAUGCUUGCCUUCCCACCAGAAAGUCCACUGCAGGGCCUGGCACUGAGCUGGCAGUCAGUGCACAUCCUGGGGUUUUAUUAUUGGUGUGGAUGUUUAAAUUAAGGAAUAAUUGAUUGUUGUUGAAGCACUUGCUGUGCAUUCAGCAAGUUAUUUGGUUUCAUUUCUGUUGCUAUGCUUGUAAUUCUAAUUCAUUUGAAGAAGAAAAAUGAACAUUCCCUUAGUGGUCACAAACUAUUUCCAAAUUCACUUUCCAUAAAGAAGGAUUUUGAAGUGAGGCCGGGCAUGGUGGCUCACGCCUGUAAUCCCAGCACUGUGGGAGGCCAAGGCAGGUGGAUCACCUGAGGUCAGGAGUUCAAGACCAGCCUGGCCAACAUGGUGAAACCCUGUCUCUACUAAAAAUACAAAAAUUAGCCAGGCAUGAUGGCAUGCGCCUGUAGUCCCAGCUUCUCAGGAGGCUGAGGCAGGAGAAUUGCUUGAACCCGGGAGGCAGAGGUUGCAGUGAGCCGAGAUUGUGCCACCGCACGCCAGCCUGGGUGACAGAGUGAGACUCCAUCUCAAAAAAAAGGAUUUUGUUUCCAAAUAGAAACAGCUUUGUGUUAUAGCAAUUUAGAUCCCGUCUCAUUUUAUUUUGUGUGUUUUUCCUAGUUCCUAAGGUCAGUCAUAGGUGUCCCCGGAAGGGAAUGGAGAGGAAUGAGGCAGGGAACUGGGACCCCCCUUCUCCUGUGCCCAAGGAUGGGCAGAGCUGUGCAGGAGCAGCACAGUGGGGAAAGCAGUCAGGGGAAGGGAGGGGCCCAUCAUCCCUUGAGUCACAUCAAGCGAAGCAAGCAACAGGAUAAAUUAGGCGUAAAGGUUUUAUCUGUGAAAGAGACUAGGAUACAUGACCAAGUGCAAAGUGUGAACCUAACUUGGAUUAUGUGUUGUUGUUUUUUUAAAAAAAAGAAAAAAGAAAAAAGCUUUAAAGACAUUCUUGGGAAAGUUGGAAAAUUUGAAGAUGGACUGGAAUGUUAGAUGAUGAUGUGGGAUUAAUGUUAAUAUGAUAGUUUUGUAGGGGUUUAUCUUUAUUCCUAGGAGAGGCAGGCUGAAGUCUGUGGGGUGAAGUAACACAAUGCUUGCAACUUACUUUCAAAUGGUAUUUGAAAAAACAUUACACAUCAUGUACACACACAGGCUCACACAUAUAUAAGAUCCAUGUGUAGAGAAGAGAGAGAAAGCAAAUAUAAUCUCCUGUUUCCCCAAGAUGUACCUGCUGAAAGGCAAAUGUGGAUCAGUUCCUGGAGACAAUGAGUUAGAGUGGAUGAAGCACAGGUUUUAGAAUCGGGCAGUUCUGGACUUAAGUUUCAGCUGUGCCACUCACUAGCUGGUGACCUUCAGUAAGUUACUUAGCCUCAGUGAAAUUCCGUUUCCACAUCUCUAGAGGGGUCCACGUCAUAGGUUGCUAUAAGGAUUAAAUGAGAUAUUGCCUUUAAGUACCGAGCUCAGCGCUGGCACACAGGCCCCUGGUAAAUAUCAGUCUCUUUCCCCAAUGUGCAAGAGUGGAGCUGGCUGUCAAUCAUUUGCUGACACUGCCUCCUACCCAACCCUGUCUUCCCAGUGCUUGGCCUUCACCGAGGCUCUCAGAGCGCGCAGUCCCUCAGGGGCGGCCCUAUGCAUGCACACAUGGCAACUGACCUGUGUCCCUACACCUCUGGGUGGGAAAGGCAAAACCCAAGCCCAGAGGAGGCCCAGUGCCACCAGGCAGAGGGAGCAGGCCAGGAGCUGGUACCAGCAAGAGUGGAUAAUGCUGCCCAAGCCUGAGUCAAACAUGUGGAAAGAAGGGGCUAUGGGGCAGGUUGGGGCAGAAGGUACCUAGUGGUGGGCAUUGCGGUCUACAAUCCAGUCAUUUUUUCUGCCCAUCCCAGUCACGCGCCCACAGUCCAUGAGGCGGUAUACCCUGCACACCUCUCUUUCAACCCCUGUUGUUUCCAAAGCAUAUUUCUCCUUUUCCGUUGCCCCCGUUUCUUCCCCUCUCAUCCAUGUCUUUGUGUGAGUGAGCAGAGGUACGGUGGUGAUCUCCCCACUCCGCUCCCUCCAGCUCCUCCUGCUCUGAUCCGGCCUCUGUGCCCACUGUAGGGUGACCGUGACAGUGCCCUCCCUUCGGUCCCCAUGGGGUGGCUGUCCAGAGUUGUUUGGACUCAUUCGCUGCCAUGACCAAGAGCAGCGUGGCCCCUAAUUGGUGGUGCAUUUCUCAGGUCUCCCUGAUGAGGGUGGCUGGCUAGGCCUGUCUUUCCACGUGCACUCACCUUUUCAGAGCCCAGGCUAGCCCAGAGACAGCUUUCUGAUGAAAGGUUAACAAGGCUGGGGUUUGCUCCUUUGAGCAGACAUAUUUGAUUUCGGGAGGAAAAACUUGCCAAUCAAAAAAGAGAAAUCAGAUUCUGGACAUUCAUAACGAUUGAGUUGAACAUUCGGGAGCUAUGUGAUUAGGCAUUCAGCGUGUCCUCCUCGGGUGGUAUUCCUCUCGUUAUAGAGAGCUGGAGAAGGCCAGAGAGCUCCACGGUGAGGCCAGGGCUCCUGAUGUACCAUGGAAGAACUGAGAAAUGUCAGCAGCUGAGUGAAAAUCCAGGUGCAAAACAGUAGUUUGCUCUCUAAGCUGUACCACCUCUGUUCAGCCCAAGUUCAUGUUGGCUGCAGAAGGGCUAGGGACCAAGCUUAGUCCACCCCUCCAGACCGUCCAGACCAUCCCUCCUUCUAGGACUUGAGCACUAUAAGGUCAAUUUAAGCAUCCCGUAUGUGCUAGGUGUUGGGAUGGCCUAAGAGUAGUGUGGGAGGGGCAUGGAGAUGAAUUGCUCACUGCCCACCAAGCUCCACACUGAGACCUGGAGGGAAUGGGUCUCUGUUCCAGCUCCAGGGAGCAUGCUAGGCCAUUCCAGUAGGUUAGCCUACUGAAUCCCUCCAGCCAACCUGUAAGGGGCUCAGGUGGUAUCCUCUCUUGGAGAGGAGGAGACAGGCUCACAGAGAAUGGGCCUUAGUCAAGAUUACACAAGUCAGAAGCAACAGGAUUCAAAGCUACAUUGUUUAUUCUAAAGCUUGGGUUCUUGCCCAACUCUGUGCUGAGAACAUGGCAGUUUCCUGGGUUGUAGUGAGAGGGCCAGUGCAGCCACCUGGGCAGGUGGCUCAGGAUCCCAGGAGGGUGGACCACAAGUGAGACUGUUCUGGUAUUCUUACAGAUCUUAGGCCCUCCUUAAUGUUUCUGGGCCUCAGUUGGAACCAAGACAAGUAAGCUGGUAUCCUGUACCUGGUGUAGGCUCAAACUUAGCCCUAGACCCCAAAGGCAUGUUGGAUGAUUUUCUGGUGUGUGUGAGAGAGUAGAAUGCAGGGUAAAAACUGAGCAUGUGUGGGAGCUAGCACUGGAGGUACCAGAGGGCAGUCCAACCCCAUACCCACAAUUACUUUGGCAUCAACCUAAUACAUUUAGCAGUGUCUACAUUUAGUUAGGGUACAUGAGACAUAAAAUCCAAAAGAGAAAUUGUUGGCUUAUGCUAGCUUCAGGUAUGGCUUGGUAUCCAGUCAUGUUCAUCAGACCCCAGUUUUUUGGUUUUUGUUUUUUGCUUUUGUUUUGCUUGAGACAGGGCCUCACUCUGUCACCCAGGCUAGAGUGCAGUGGCAUGAUCUCGGCUCACCGCAGCCUCAACCUUCCAGGCUCAAGCCAUCCUCCUGCCUCAGCCCCCAAGUUGCUGGGACUAUAUAGGUGCACACCACCGCACCUGGCUAAUUUUUUCUUCUUCAAUAUUUACUUUAAGUUCCAGGGUACACAUGCAGGAUGUGCGGGCUUGUUACAUAGGUAAACAUGUGCCAUGGUGGUUUGCUGCACAGAUGAACCCAUCACCUAGGUAUUAAGCCCAGCAUCCCUUAGCUAUUCUUCCUGAUGCUCUGGCUCGCCUCCCCACCCACCACUGACAGGCUCCAGUAUGUGUUAUUCCCCCAGUGUGUCCAUGUGUUCUCAUCAUUCAGCUCCCACUUGUAAGUGAGAAUGUGCGGUGUUUGGUUUUGUAUUCCUGCACUAGUUUGCUGAGGAUAAUGGUUUCCAACUCCAUCCAUGUCCCUGCGAAGGACAUGACCUCAUUUCUUUUUAUGGCUGCAUAGUAUUCCAUGGUGUACAUUUUCUUUUUUCAGUCUAUCAUUGAUGAGCAUUUGGGUUGACUCCAUGUCUUUGCUAUUGUGAAUAGUGCUACAGUGACAUGUGCAUGUAUCUUUAUAGUAGAAUAAUUGAUAUUCCUUUGGGCAUAUAACCAGUAAUGGAUUGCUGGGUCAAAUGGUAUUUAUGCUUUAGAUCUUUAUGGAAUCACCACACUGUCUUCCACAAUGGUUGAACUAAUUUACACUCCCACCAACCAUAUAAAAGUGUUCCUUUUUCUCUACAACCUCUCCAGCAUCUGUUGUUUCUUGACUUUUUAAUAAUCGCUAUUCUGACUGGUGUGAGAUGGUAUCUCAUUGUGGUUUUGACUUGCAUUUCUCUAAUGACUACUGAUGUUGAGCUUUUUUUCAUAUGUUCAUUGGCCACGUGAAUGUCUUCUUUUGAGAAGUGUCCAUGUCCUUUGCUCACUUUUUAAUGGAAUUUUUUUUUCUUGUAAAUUUGUUCAAGUCCCUUGUAGACUCUGGAUAUUAGGCCUUUGUCAAUGGAUCGAUUGCAAAAAUUUUCUCCCAUUCUGUAGGUUGUCUGUUCACUCUGAUGAUAAUUUAUUUUGCUGUGCAGAAGCUCUUUAAUUUAAUUAGAUCCCAUUUGUCAAUUUUUGCUUUUGUUGCACAUUGCUUUUGGCAUUUUCGUCAUGAAAUUUUUGCCCAUACCUAUGUCCUGAAUGGUAUUGCCCAGAUUUUCUUCUAGGAUUUUUGUAGUUUUGCAUUAUACAAUUAGGUCUUUAAUCCAUCUUGGGUUAAUUUUUGUAUAUGUAGUGUAAGGAAGGGGUCUACUUUCAAUUUUCUGCAUAUCGCUAGCCACUUCUCCCAGCACCAUUUGUUAAAUAGGGAAUCCUUUCCCCAUUGCUUUUUGGGUUUUUGUUUGUUUGUUUUUUUGAGACAGAGCCUUGCUGUGUCACCCAGGCUGGGGGGCAGUGAUGCAAUCUCGGCUCACUGCAACCUCCACAUCCCAGGUUCAAGCGAUUCUCAUACCUCAGCCUCCCAAGUAUCGGAUUAUAGGUGUGUGCCACCAUACUCAGCUAAUUUUUGUAUUUUUUAGUAGAGAUGGGGUUUCACCAUGUUAGCCAGGCUGGUCUUGAACUCCCAGCCUCAACUGGUCCACCCUCCCCGGCCUCCAAAAGUGCUGGGAUUACAGGCACAAGCCACUGCACCUGGCCCCUAUUGCUUGUUUGUUGAAGAUCAGAUGGUUGUAGGUGUGCAGUUUUAUUUCUGAGGUUAUAUUCUGUUCCAUUGGUCUAUAUCUGUUUUUGUACAAGUACCAUGCUGUUUUGGUUACUGUAGCCUUGUAGUAUAGUUUGAAGUCAAGUAGCAUGAUGCCUCCAGCUUUGUCCUUUUGCUUAUGAUUGUCUUGGCUAUUCGGGCUCUUUUUUGGUUCUAUAUGAAUUUUAAAAUAGUUUUUUCUAAUGCUGUGAAGAAUGUCAAUGGUAGUUUAAUGGGAUUAGCAUUGAAUCUAUAAAGUACUUUGGGUAGUAUGGCCAUUUUCAUGAUAUUGAUUCUUUCUAUCCAUGAGCAUGAGUGUUUUUCCAUGUGCUUGUGUCCUCUCUUAUUUCCUUGAGCAGUGGUUUGUGGUUCUCCUUGAAGAGGUCCUUCACUUCCCUUGAUAGCUGUCUUCCUAUAUAUUUUAUUCUUUUGUAGCAAUUGUGAAUGGGAGUUCAUUCAUGAUUUGGCUCUCUGCUUUGUGUAUAGGAAUGCUAGCUAUUUUUGCACAUUGAUUUUGUAUCCUGAGACUUUGCUGAAGUUGCUUAUCAGCUUAAGAAGCUUUUGGGCUGAGACGAUGGGGUUUUCUAUAUAUAGGAUCAUGUCAUCUGCAAAUAAAGAUAAUUUGACUUCCUGUCUUUCUAUUUGAAUGCCCUUUAUUUCUUUCUCUUGCCUGAUUGCCCUGGCCAGAACUUCCAAUACUGUGUUGAAUAGGAGUGGUGAGAGAGGGCAUCCCUGUCUUGUGCUGGUUUUCAAGGGGAAUGUUACCAGUGUUUGCCCAUUCAGUAUGAUAUUGGCUGUGGGUUUGUCAUAUAUGGCUCUUACUAUUUUGAGGUAUAUUUUUUCAAUACCUAGUUUAUUGGGAGUUUUUAACAUGAAGGAAUGUUGAACUUCAUCAAAGCCCUUUUCUGCAUCUAUUGAGAUAAUCAUGUGGUUUUUGUCUUUAGUUCUGUUUAUGUGAUGAAUUACAUUUAUUGAUUUGUGUAUGUUGAACCACCCUUGCUUCCUGGGGAUGAAGCCAACUUGAUCAUGGUGGAUAAGUUUUUGAUGUGCUGCUGGAUUCGUUUUGGCUUGUUUAAUUUUUGUAUUUUUUGUAGAGACAGGGUUUCAUCAUGUUGCCCAGGCUGGUCUCGAACUCCUGAGCUCAAGCGAUCUACCUGCCUCAGCCUCCCAAAGUGUUGGGAUUACAGGCGUGAGCCACUGCGCCCAACCUAGACCCCAUUUUUUUAUUUUGCCUCAUUUAUUGGCCUUGCCUCUUCUGCUACGGCCAUUCUCAGGCAGGCUUUCCCCUCCUGGUGGCAAGAUGCCUGCAAUCCUUCCAGGUGCAAGACCAACAGGAAAGUGACUGUCACUUCCUAGUAACUCCCACGCAAGGCACGGCAUUGACUCGCUGGACUGACUGAUUAUAUGCCCAUCGGAACCAAUUAUUGAGGCCAAGGGUUUUUUGUGUGCUGCAGGUAGGGCCCCACCUGAAGCAUAUACCUAAGGGGUCAUUCCUGAAAGGGAAAUUGGGGCCAUUAUCAAAAGAAGGGAGAGAAGAUCAAGUUGACAAUGUGCACAGAAGCCAAACAGGAGACACUGUCUCAGCUCUUUGUCCACUUGUCUCACAGCAGAGAACGGUUCAUACCAGACCUGUGGGGAUCCUAAAACCGAGAGAGCAUGCAGGGCUGAGAGUCAAGGUCAGACAUUAACCAGGGCACCAGAUAGAGGAGGGACAGAAGAGAAAUGGCAGGUUAGCGCAUGGCAGACCAGGGAGGUAGGAGGCAGGGUGUAGAGAUGGGCACAGCUGUCUGCCGUUGCCUGCGAUAGCUUCUGGAGACUCAAGUGUGACAAAGUCCACUGCAGUCCCGGGGCUAGGAGAGGAGAAGGGUAGAAGCUAAGAACCUAGGUCAUUCGUUCAGCAAAUCAUCACUGAUGCCUACUCUGUGCCACAUCUGUGAAAACAGAGAUGGCAAUGACACGGUUCCUGACUUCAGGGGUCUAACAUUCUCGUGGUGAGUGGUUCAACGUAAUCCUGAUGGACAGAAUCCAUCUGGUAGUUUUGAAAGGCCCAGAUUUGUGCUUGUGUGAUCAUGCCAUAGGGCAUCUCUAAGUGCCCUUUUUGUUUGUUCUAAACCCCAACAAGUUUGGUCCUCAGGGUGGUCUCCCCACCAGCAUUCUCAUGAGGUGCCCAUCAGCUCCUCACGGCCAGCUUGCUAGAGAUCACUGUGAAAUAGAUGGAAUGUUUUGUUAACACCCUUGCUUUUUAUCUGCUUCAAGGACUAGGCAGAGAGCUUGUCUUUCUAAGAUGGGAGUGUGCAUCUUCUUCAGGCUGUGUCUGAGAUGCAUGGGGAGGGUUCCAAACCAGAGAAACUAAACACAGUGGCUGUUCCAGGCUGUUCUGCGAUGAGGUGGCAACUGAUUUCAUGUUAAGUAUCUGCCCCUGGUCCAGGCGUCCCCACUUGCUUUCCACAGCCAGUUGCAAUGGACAUUUCUCACCUUUUAAAUAAUUUCUUUGGUGCAAGUUAUGGUCUCCAGAAAAGCUCAACUAAAAUACACAAAGAGGAACAGAAACUAGGCUGGCUGCAGAAUGGCUGACUGAUUGCCCUGUAGAGUCCAGCCAGAGAGGGAGGUCUGAGCUGGGCUUUGCACCUAGGACCUGUGUUUGGUCCUCCCUUCCCUUAGAUGGAGCUCCUCCCUGGCUCCAUUCUGCCUCUAACUCUACUCCCUUAGCAGCCACGAGGAGCUCUACCUGUGGUUUCUAGCACCACCUUUGUUCUGGGAGCUCCAGGUUUCUGUUUCUAGCUCAUUCCUGUUUCACAAGCUUCAGCUACUAGAAUGUCUUAGUCAGACUUCCCAAACCAGCUGUACCCCAGUUCCACCAAGGUGUCAGCCCCUCUGUACCCAUACAUUCCUCAUAUCCCUGGGGUCCUGUGUCUCUCUCCUCGACUGGUCUGUGAGGCACAAUGGGUAUCAGAAAGCAUCAGCACACGUUGAGAUAGGCAGGGCCUGCAGCCUCCCGAAUGUGGCACCUCUCCAGGAUUGUCUCCCUGACCACUGGUUUGCCUGCAUGGUCAAGAGGACGUACCCAGCCUCCAGGACCCUCCCUGCCAGAAAUCACCACCACCCCUACCAAGCCCACCCUGACCACAGCUAGGCCUUCUAGUCUGGAGCUCCCUGCCAUCCUCCACUCCUGGCAGUUCCUGCCCACCCUCCAGGACUCUGUGAAGUGCCCCUGCCCUGGGCAGAGUCCCUUCUUCUCUAGUCCCUAGCGCCUCGUAUUUAUUUGUUCACCAGCUCUUCAUGGGCAUCUGCACUGGGGGACCCAGGGAUGAAUCAGCCCCUACCAUCUCUGCUGCCAGGAAUGAUUUUCCUCUUCUGUUCCACCUGAACAGAAAAUCCUCCCAACCCUUCAAGGCCCUGCUCAGGCAUCGCCUUCCCUUGACAAGCCCCCACCUCCACCGACUUCUCCAAGCCCAGUCAUUCCCUUGCUGCUCUGAGCCGGCACUGUCCCUAUGCUGGCUUGCUGGGGAUGCAUUUAUACCCUGUCCCACAGAAAAGGACAGAAUUGGCCUUCUCUGUAUCCUUGGCACCCUCACAGGGCCUGGCACAGACGAGCUGCCCAUGAGAGUUUGGGGAAUGACCAAGUGGUGAAUGAGUGCGGGCAGGAAAGGCAGUGACGUGGGGAAGAGGCGAGGCCAGGUCCACUCACUCCUUGUGCCCUUGAGUAGUCAGUCGGUUCAGCAGAGCAAGAGAAAUCCAGCAAAAGGCAGUGACUUGUUCUGCGGCGCCUGCACGCGCUUUAGAAUCCCCGCACGCGGCGCCAGGUUGUGAGAGACAGGAUCCUGAGUCCCCCAAGGCUCCACCUUCAGCGGUGUGACAGCGGGGCUUCUCUGCCAAAGGACUGGCCAGAGCCUACAAACGGCAUUUCUUUAAAGGUCUGUGUCGGAGCUGCUCAGAAUCCAGCUCCCUGCCGGGGAGAUAUUGAGCCCAACAGGACAAGAGCAGGAAAUCUGAUUCAGCGAGACCAGAGGAGACAUUUUCUCAGAUUAGAAUUCUCUGUGCCAGAGGUGGGGAGUUUAUCACAGCAGGGAAGGGGAAAUAAAACAUAAAAUAUUGAAAAUAAAUUAUAUACCACAUGCGAGAUCACCUUAGAGAGUCAGCUCUGUAUCUGUGGCUGUGCAGGGAGUCCCCGCCCCAUGGUCACAGGAGUGCUGUGCCAGAGGCUGCUUGUCGCACAUCCACCAUCAGUCCCUAGCCCUGGCAGAGCCAGGUAGUGCCUGCGGGCUAAGGAAAUUAUUAACCUGGCUGUGCCCAGAGGAAGGGAUGGCAAGGACUAACCAAGAGAUGGAGAGUAAAAAGGGGUUAGGUGGACCUAGGGGUUUUCAUUACAAUGUAGACCUCCUGUGUCUCAGCCAAGCCCCUUCACAAACUUCGUCUCACUUAAUGUUCUCAACAGCCCUCUAAGACUGAUGCAGUUAUGAUGAUCCCCAGAUAGCUGAUGCUCAGAGAGGUUAAGCACCUUGACCAAGGUCACACAGUAAGUGGCAGAGCAAGAAUUAAAAUCCAGGCCUAUCUGAUGCUGGAACCUGGGCUCUCCCCACCCCAGGUGGGGGAGCUUGAAUUUUAUCCCAUAGGUGCCUAGGAGCCAACGAGGGUUGUAUUCAGAGAAAUAGCAGCUGGGAAUAUGUAUGCUGGGCCACUGUGGAAGGGGAUGGAAGUAGUUGAGGCAGAGAGACCACUGAUGAUCCCACGGACAUUGCUCAGGCCAGGGCUGGUGGGAGCCUAAUCUAGGACACUGCUUCUGGGGGUAAAGAUGAGAAAAUCAUCCUAGAGACAUUUAGGAGACCCAAAGGACACAACUUGGCGGGCAGCCGGAUGUCCUGCGUGGGAACUGUUGAAGCUGAUCAUAGAAUAGCACAGGGCUGGACACAGGCUGUGUUCCUCUUCAUCCAGCCAGCAUGCCCCAGUGAGGCUUGAAGUACAGUCCGUGAGGAAGGGAUGUCCCUUGGGGUGUGCAGGAUUGAUGGACACCCUCCCUCAGCAACCCAGACUAGAAGUUUCUGCUCAGGGGCAGAAUAGCCUGCUUGGAGGAAAGAGGGUACAGCUCCCCCAACCCUCACUGUCCCUGCAUUUUCCCCAGGGCUGUCUACCAACCACCUUCCUUUUUAUACUCUCCCAGAGUGCUGUAAGCACCAGGAUACCCGUAACUUACUCCACCCCCUCUCCCCAGCCUAGGGUGUGGAAUGUUAUGGCUCCUUCCCUCCAGGUUGCCAGCUCUUCAGCCCCCAGGCCAUUUCCACCAAGGAUGAUGUACAGUAUUAUGCUAAACCAACUUUACGGGUAGCCCCUUAAAAUGCAGGCCUGUACCUGUGAUGGAUGGAGAACAUCCAGUUGUUUAGCCAACCACUUACAGUUUGUUGCAAACUUGCAAGAACCACACACGGGCCUCUUGUUAGGCCUGUUAUGCCAAGGACCCCAUAAAUAAACAGUAGCGUGUAUCUUGGUGCAUCAGGGCUGGAGUAUGGAAAUAGAAGUACUGUAUAAAUAAUGCAUAUUUACAAAAUAAAUAUAUCCCAUACAUGAGCGUGUGCAGCCAUAACCAAAGCACCUAGUUUAACAACCACGGAAAGCUUUGAGGGCCUGCCAAGUGAUCAGCUUCCAUCCAUCAGUGUGCACCAGCAUUAGAAAUGACCGCCGAAGGGAGGGGGUCCUCCUGCACGCUGACCUUGAGGCCUUUGCAUUGAGGCAAGUGGUGAGAUUGCAGGUGGGCACCCUGACACACAGCUUCUCUGCCAAGGUGUGAAACCUACCACAGCCAUGUGUUCCUGCAGAUGUCUUAAGGUCUACCGCCAAGCAGAAGGCUGAUGAGCGCCGAGUUGCAGGACGUAAUGGGUUGUACCUACAGGAAGAGGGCUGGCUGGGGGAGGGAGAGAUUUCCUAAUUAUGCAGAUUCACUUUGGCUUGCAAAAGGGGCCGGUGAGUUGCCUUUCCAGGGGACUCUUACCGGAGCCCUGUAACUUUCAGCCAUUCACCCUGAAGGCAGGGCUGAGCUUUCGGGAAGUCAGUGUCCCGUCUCUGCCGCCCCAUUUUGAGCUCUGAACCCCACCGGGCAUCCGGCUCUAGCAUCUGGAGCUUGGAAGAAGCAGCUGACAGAAUGGCCGCUGGAGUGGGCGCCCCUCCCCUUGGUUGUAAUGGCACAAUGCUGGAUUUCAGUAUUUUAAAUGAAAAAUAUAUGCAGUUAGCUGUGCGCUGACAAUGUCCUUGAGGAUUUGACAGUGAGAUUUUCCAGCAGUUGGUCUUCGUUAGGAUCCUGGCGGUGUUUAAUAAGGCAGUCGAACUGCUGGCACCUUGGGUUCCUGUUUGUUCUCCGAGGGCUCAGGGGCUGCUGCGGUAAGCACAUCGACCAGAGCUGAUCAUUACAAGGGCGUACGCCACCAUGAAUAAAAAUGUCACACGUUUUCCCAUCUCACAGCAGUACAAAAUGUCAGUCCUGUCAAACACACAUUGCAGGGAGCUGUGUGCAGUCCGUACAAAUUGGAGAGCCGCAUAUUCCCCCAGCCUUCUGAUAUUCUUCAUUUGAAGCUGAAGAAAAACAGUUGUUAACCUAUUAGCUAGGAUUUUAAACUCUGCUGAGGCGGUGGAUGGGUAGACUUUGACACAGAUAGAAAUGUAUUCCAAGGUCCAGGAAUUUUAAAACCAGGUUCUCCGUCCAUUUGUUCUGAGGGAAGGAAAAAAAAAAAAAACCUUCUGUCUGGUGAACCUGACUAUCUUUCUUUAACAGACACACUAGGGAAAUUUUGGGAUAUUUCAUAUCUAAGCUUCCCAUUGCUUCCACGUUUGCAUUCCACUCAAAAAGUCUAUUGCUUUGGGGGAUGGCCCUGGGGCUCAACCUGUUAGGCUAGGAAACCUGUAGGUAGAGGGUUUUUCCUGAUCAGAAGCAUGCCAGGAAUGUUGCCAGUCUUGCAGACAAAGUAACUCAAAUCAUGGGGACAAUGACUGGCGGGUCUGGCAUUAUUCAGAUGCUGGGUGAUGGCUUCACUGAUAAUUUGAUGCUAGUUCCCCACUCUUGGGCAGCCAUUUACUUUAACUUGACCGCGUGCCAGGCCUUGUGCCAGGAGCCAGAUGUGAACCCUCAAGGACUCACCUUCUUAGGGGAAGGACAGAGGUAGGAGUGCCCGACUUUUGUGGGCCAGGAAUAGAGAGAGAACUUCUGGGGGAAGGGAACAGAGUCGUGAGGGAUGCAGGGAUCCAUCAGGUGGGUGAGUGAGGGAAGGGCUUAUAGGACCAGCAUGUGUGUUGUGAAGGGCCAUGGCCCGUGAGGGGGCUGGCUGGAAAGAAGGGGCUUCUUGUGGUGGGGUUUAUCGGGGGCAGGGCCAGGUCUUGAAUGGCAUGCUGGGGACAGGGAUGUGAGCAACUCUCCUGGGCUGCCAGUGGCAGGGAAAGCAGUUGGAGGCUCGUGGUGGCCUGGCCAAGGAGUCCUGGACUCCCUUUCUAGAUAGAGGGUGCUAUGCACUCCUCUCUGGACCUCUGCAAAAUGAGGAGAAUUCUUCUCAUUUCCUAGUUGCAUCCUGUUAGGGUGGACAUCAUUCCAGAGAUGAUAAAUGAGCCUGGUUUUGCUGAGCUGGCCCUGGUCCUUAAAUGUACUGAGCAAAUUCUCACUGAGUAGGGACACGGGCCUGGUGAAAUGCAGGCGGCUGCAAAGACAAACCUUUCUGUGUGGUCAGAACAGACUUAGCAGGACAAAAGUCUCAAAGGAUGUCAGAGGGAGGACUUUCUGGGGAGAGAGAGGAGCGGACCCGAGGAGAUACGUUUUAACAUCUUCUUCUGCUGUUGGUAUGUCGGGUCUCCUGGGAGCAGCGUGGGCUUCUUUGGAGUCAGGCGUACUUGGGCUUGGAUCCUGGCUCUGCCACCCGUUAGCUGUCAGGCCGGGCCUGGGCAAGUCACUGAGUGACAUGGCCUCGGUUUCUUCAUCUUUCACAUUCUUGGAGGGUUGCUGAGAUGAAUAGAGACCUCGCAUGUAGAUCUCCUAGCACGGGGCCUGGUACCUAGCAAGUGUCAGAAAAUAGUAGCCCCAGAGAGGAGAUCAUUUCCCCCAACAUCUGGAAGCCCCUCUAACCUCACCUCGUGUCCCCCUCCUCCUGGGAAUGUCACCCAGGCACCCUCGACAGCAUCCUAGAUGCAUCCCAGCAGCAAGGCGCCUGCCUCCUGCUUCUGUCUGGGCAAAGAAUGGCAUACGUCAGCGAGGUCCCUGCCCCUGCCCAGGCACCAGCCGCAUCUGGUGCCCGACCUCCGGCCACCAAUGGGAUGCCACCUAUUCAGACUGUGCACCUGCACCCGACUAAAAACAAAGGGCUCCCCUCCCCCUGCCCCACUGCUGGCCCUCCUCCCUCCCCCGCCUCUGUCCCCCAAGCGGCUAGGGUCACCCGGCCCCCACGCAGCCUUCCCUCACAGCUGCCUCGCUGCUUUUGUUCAGCAUGUGAACUUCCCCGUCAGCCGAGCUCUUUGCACGGGAAGUAAUCAGGGAUCUUGACAAGGCUUCAAACCACAAAUGCCACUACAAAUUAACCAGCACCACUACAAAAUACUACUCCUGUCAACAUCGGGGAAGAAUGCACUGCUCUUCAGGACCAGUCUGAGAUGUCUUUCAGCUCAGCACUCACUCACGGCAAAGAGAGUGCCCGGACCCAGCCGGAGAGAGUCGUUGACAGGACUGGCGAGCCCCUGAAUCCUGAGCGCGCUCUCUCCGGAGAUCAUCUCUGUGAGACCCCGCGGCAGGUGCUGCGGCUUUUCUUCCCGGACCCCCUUCGAUCCUGAGCACCCCCUCAUCCCCCUCGCAGGUGGCGCCUCUGGAGGGCAAGUUGUGGGGCACCCAGAAACCUCACUGUGGAGUCUGCCGUUCAGAGUGAAGCCCAGCCCGACCUCUCUGCGUCCUACCUAUGUGCUGUGCCUUUGGGCAAGGGGCUUCCCUUUCCCUGUCUACAGAGCGGCAAUCAUAAUAGAGCCUCUGUCUCAGAGUCGCCAGGACCACUGGGAUAUCCUGAGUAAUACCUGGCCCCUCCCAGCCUCCCUUCCUUUCCCUGAAGAAACAGGUCCUUGUUGCCCUGUGUGAGUGGACUCUCAGCAAGUGGAAACCUCUUCCUCAGCGUGACGUGGAAGUCCUUCCUGUACAGCAUCUUGCAAGGAAUAUCCCUCUAGAGUGACAGCUUGUUAUCUCUGCAAAUGCUUCAGGCCUCAGGAUCCCCACAUUUCCUCUGGGUGCCCCGCUGAGUGGCUCAGGCAAGGAGCAUGCUGUACGCUACGUGACACCAGGGCCUGGUCUUCUCCAGCUGCCCUGGCUGAAGCUCUGAAGUGGAGGCAAGUAUUUGAUCCUCCCCCGCAAGCAGCACAGCCCUCAUCCAGGGCGGACAGAGAGGAUCGGAGACAGCGAUGGGCGCUGGGGGCUAGGUGAGAGCUGUGCCUGCAAGAGAGCUUCUUGGGCAUCUCAAAGGAGACACUCCACAAAAAUAUCGCUUCAAUGCACUCCUUUUUGGAGGCAUAUCAAAAGCAGCCCUCUUUUAUUUCCAUGCCUUGCAUAAUAGCAGAUUUCCAGUCCCAAAGUGUAGAGGAGCCUUGCUCUCGGCGCAGAGGCCCUUUGUAAAACUACAGAAGGCUUUGUCUUCCCUCCCAACCGGGUCUGUUUCAUGCAUAGGUCAGAGCAUUGAUGUGGCUACUAGCCAGGAAAAAUUAACCAGGUGAACACUCUCCUCAUUAAACAGCGACAGAGUUUAA